AGACCAGGAAGCGGAUAGCGUGGAGUGACGGUGCCACCGCGGCGCAUGGAGUUUCGCUCUUGUUGCUCAGGCUGGAGUGCAAUGGUGUGAUCUCGGCUCACUGCAACCUCCGCCUCCCGGGUUCAAGCGAUUCUCCUGCCUCAGCCUCUCGAGUAGCUGAGAUUACAGGCAUGAUCCAUUGCUCCCAGCCACCCAUGUAUUCCUGAUUGAAAAAAUUUGCUUAUGUCUUAGUUCUACAGCUGACCCUCUUUCGCUAUUUUCAAGAGUAUUGCCCGGGCUGUGAGUGCAGUCUCAUGAUCUUGGGUCACUGCAACCUCUGUUUCCUGGGUUCAAGUGAUUCUUGUGCCUCAGCAUCCCACGUAGCUGAGAUUACAGGAUUGACUUCUAAAGACUCUUGGUACGUGAGGAAGAAACCCGGAAGAGGAAGAGGAGAGCAAAGGAGUCAGGGAUGGCUUUUUCUCAGGGUCUAUUGACAUUCAGGGAUGUGGCCAUAGAAUUCUCUCAGGAGGAGUGGAAAUGCCUGGACCCUGCUCAGAGGACUCUAUACAGGGACGUGAUGCUGGAGAAUUAUAGGAACCUGGUCUCCCUGGAUAUCUCUUCCAAAUGCACGAUGAAGGAGUUCUUGUCAACAGCGCAAGGCAACAGAGAAGUGUUCCAUGCAGGGACAUUGCAAAUACAUGAAAGUCAUCACAAUGGAGAUUUUUGCUACCAGGAUGUUGAUAAAGAUAUUCAUGACUAUGAAUUUCAAUGGCAAGAAGAUGAAAGAAAUGGCCAUGAAGCACCCAUGACAAAAAUCAAAAAGUUGACAGGUAUUACAGAACGAUAUGAUCAAAGUCAUGCUAGAAACAAGCCUAUUAAAGAUCAGCUUGGAUCAAGCUUUCAUUCGCAUCUGCCUGAAAUGCACAUAUUUCAGACCGAAGAGAAAAUUGAUAAUCAAGUUGUGAAGUCUGUCCACGAUGCUUCCUUGGUUUCAACAGCCCAAAGAAUUUCUUGUAGGCCCAAAACCCAUAUAUCUAAUAACCAUGGGAAUAAUUUCUGGAAUUCUUCAUUACUCACACAAAAACAGGAAGUACACAUGAGAGAAAAAUCUUUCCAAUGUAAUGAGAGUGGCAAAGCCUUUAAUUACAGCUCACUCUUAAGGAAACAUCAGAUAAUCCAUUUAGCAGACAAAUAUAAAUGUGAUGUAUGUGGCAAGCUCUUUAAUCAGAAGCGAAACCUAGCAUGCCAUCGUAGAUGUCACACUGGUGAGAAUCCUUACAAGUGUAAUGAGUGUGGCAAGACCUUCAGUCAGACGUCAUCCCUUACAUGCCAUCGUAGACUUCAUACUGGAGAGAAACCUUACAAAUGUGAAGAAUGUGACAAAGCUUUCCAUUUCAAAUCAAUACUUGAAAGACAUAGGAUAAUUCAUACUGAAGAGAAACCAUAUAAGUGUAAUGAGUGUGGCAAGACCUUUAGGCAGAAGUCAAUCCUUACACGCCAUCAUCGACUUCAUACUGGAGAGAAACCUUACAAGUGUAAUGAGUGUGGCAAGACCUUUAGUCACAAGUCAUCCCUUACAUGCCAUCAUAGACUUCAUACUGGAGAGAAACCCUACAAAUGUAAUGAGUGUGGCAAGACCUUUAGUCACAAGUCAUCCCUUACAUGCCAUCGUAGACUUCAUACUGGAGAGAAACCUUACAAAUGUGAAGAAUGUGACAAAGCUUACAGUUUCAGAUCAAAUUUUGAAAUACAUCGGAAAAUUCAUACUGAAGACAAUGCUUACAAGUGUAAUGAGUGUGGAAAGACCUUUAGCCGGACAUCAUCCCUUACAUGCCAUCGUAGACGUCAUACUGGAGAGCAACCUUACAAAUGUGAAGAAUGUGACAAAGCUUUCCGUUUCAAAUCAAACCUUGAAAGACAUAGGAGAAUUCAUACUGGAGAGAAACCAUACAAGUGUAAUGAGUGUGGCAAGACCUUUAGUCGGAAGUCAUACCUCACAUGCCAUCAUAGACUUCAUACUGGAGAGAAAGCUUACAAGUGUAAUGAGUGCGGCAAGACCUUUAGUUGGAAGUCAUCCCUUACCUGCCAUCGUAGACUUCAUUCUGGAGAGAAACCUUACAAGUGUAAGGAGUGUGGCAAGACCUUCAAUCAGCAGUUAACCCUUAAACGCCAUCGUAGACUUCAUAGUGGAGAGAACCCUUACAAAUGUGAAGAUAGUGACAAAGCUUACAGUUUCAAAUCAAACCUUGAAAUACAUCAGAAAAUUCAUACUGAAGAGAAUCCUUACAAGUGUAAUGAGUGUGGCAAGACCUUCAGUCGGACGUCAUCCCUUACAUGCCAUCGUAGACUUCAUACCGGAGAGAAACCUUACAAAUGUGAAGAAUGUGACAAAGCUUUCCGUGUGAAAUCAAACCUUGAAGGACAUAGGAGAAUUCAUACUGGAGAGAAACCUUACAAGUGUAAUGAGUGUGGCAAGACCUUUAGUCGGAAGUCAUAUUUUAUAUGCCAUCAUAGACUUCAUACUGGAGAGAAACCUUAUAAGUGUAAUGAGUGUGGCAAGAACUUUAGUCAGAAGUCAUCCCUUAUAUGCCACCAUAGACUUCAUACUGGAGAGAAACCUUACAAGUGUAAUGAGUGUGGCAAGACCUUUAGUCAGAAGUCAAACCUUACAUGCCAUCGUAGACUUCAUACUGGAGAAAAACAAGUGUAAUGAAUGUGGUGAGGUUUUUAAUCAACAAGCACACCUUGCAGGUCAUCAUAGAAUUCAUACUGGGGAGAAACCUUAGAAAUGUGAAGCAUGUGAUAAAGUUUACAGUGGCAAAUCAAGCCUCAGAAGACAGGAGAAUUCAUACUGGAGAGAAAGCUUAUAAAUGUGAAGAAUGUCACAAAGUUUACAGUCGCACAUCAAACCGUGAAAGACAGGAGAAUUCAUACUGGAGAGAAACCAUAAAAAUGUAAGAGUUUGUGACAAGGCUUUUGGGCAUGAUUCGCACCUGGCACAACAUGCUAGAAUUCACACUGGAGAGAAACCUUACCAGUGUAAUGAGUGUGGCAAAGCCUUUAGUAGGCAGUCAACACUUGUUUACCGUCAGGCAAUCCAUGGUGUAGGGAAACUUUACUAAGGUAAUGAUUGUCACAAAGUCUUCAGUAAUGCUACAACCAUUGUGAAUCACUGGAGAAUCCAUAAGGAAGAGAGAUCAUACUAGGGUAAUAAAUGUGGCAGAUUUUUCAGACAUUGUUCAUACCUUGCAGUUCAUCGGUGAACUCAACGCUGGAGAGAAACCUUACAAAUGUCAUGACUGUGGCAAGGUCUUCAGUCAAGCUUCAUCCUAUGCAAAACAUAGGAGAAUUCAUACAGGAGAGAAACCUCACAUGUGUGAUGAUAGUGGCAAAGCCUUCACUUCACACCUCAUGAGACAUCAGAGAAUGCAUACUGGACAGAAAUCUUACAAAUGUCAUCAAUGUGCCAAGGUCUUCAGUCUGAGUUCACUCCUUGCAGAAUAUGAGAAAAUUCAUUUUGGAGGUAGUUGGUCCAUAUGCAAUGAGUAGAGCAAACCAUCAAGCAUUAAUUGACAUUAGGGUCAAUUCAGCAUUGACUUGAGUUUGUAUUGACUUAACAUUGAGUUCAAGCAUUAAUUGACAUUAGUGUUUAUGUUAAGAGGAUUGGGCCAGGCACAUCAGCUUACACCUGUAAUCUGAGCGCUUUGGGAGGCCAAGGUGGGUAGAUCACUUGAGGUCAGGAGUUUGAGAUCAGCCUGGCCAACAGACGUGAGCCAUUUUCCCAGCCUGUUUUUUGUUUCUUUAAAAAAACUGAUAGGGAUUUUUAUGGAUAUCAUGUUGAAUCUAAAUCACAUUGGGUUAUUAUAUAAUCAUUUCACAAUAUUAAUUUUUCCAAGCUAUCAAUAUGGGUUGUAGCUCAAUGUUUUUAAUCAUUUUGAUCAAUGUUUGUAGAUUUCAAGGUACAAACUUCUGACCUUUGUACGUUUAUUUCUAAGUAUUUCUUUAAGUUCUCCAGCAAAUGGAAGUGUUUUAAAAUUUUCUUUUAAAAUUGUUUAUUGUUAAAGUAUGGAAAUUCAACUAAUUUUUGGUGCUGAUACUGUAUUGUGCAAAUCCACUGACUAUGUUACUUAGUUCCAGUAGUAUUUUGGUUGGCUCUUUGUGAUUUUCUACACAGAAGAUUAUGUCAUCUACAAACAAAUAUAAUUUUACUUCUUACUUUCUGA